GACUUCCGGGUCGCGGUGCUUGAAGGGAGUGUUCCGUCGUUUCCGUUGCCGGCUGUUUGCAGUGGGGAAACCGAGGCAGCUCCUGCUCCCCCUAGUUCUUCCGCUCCUGUGAGGUGGCUGCUGUUUCUUUUCCUCUUGCCCCGGAUGCCUCGGUGCGGCUGCACUGAGAGCGCGCGGGCUCGCGAGCCCCGCGGGGUUCUGCGGGAACCCGGGGGCGCCUGGGCCGGCGGGUCUUUGUGCGAGCCCUGCCCUCCCAUUCGCGGGCGGCGCGCGAGGGGGGUCGGCGCAGAGACGCCCAGAGCCCUGGGGUGCUCAGGCGCCGCUACGCGUGCAUCCCCUCUGCUCGGCAGUUCUGCGCUUUUGUCCUAAUGAGCGCGGACUAGAUGGCUUGAUUUUCAAGAUAAUGAUCAACCCAGCUGUGCUAUGCGCUCUUUCUGCACUGACCUGCGGGAAAAAAAAAUGUUUAUUUCUUUGUGGGAGUUCUUCUAUGGGCACUUUUUUCGAUUUUGGAUGAAAUGGCUAUUACGACAGAUGACUGGGAAGUGUGAAUUGCAGCGAAUAUUUGAUACCUAUGUAGGUGCACAAAGGACACACAGGAUAGAAAAUUCCUUGACAUACUCCAAGAAUAAGGUUUUACAGAAGGCGACACAUGUUGUUCAGAGUGAAGUGGACAAAUAUGUAGAUGAUAUUAUGAAGGAAAAGAAUAUUAACCCUGAGAAGGAUGCCAGUUUUAAAAUAUGCAUGAAGAUGUGCUUACUGCAGAUAACUGGUUAUAAACAGCUGUAUUUGGAUGUAGAAAGUGUGAGGAAAAGGCCAUAUGAUUCUGAUAACCUACAGCAUGAAGAGCUACUCAUGAAGCUUUGGAAUCUUCUAAUGCCCACGAAGAAGUUAAACGCUAGAAUCUCCAAGCAGUGGGCUGAAAUUGGUUUUCAGGGUGAUGAUCCCAAGACAGACUUCAGAGGCAUGGGCAUACUUGGGUUAAUCAAUCUUGUGUAUUUCAGUGAAAAUUACACUAGUGAAGCUCAUCAGAUUCUUUCCCGUUCAAAUCAUCCAAAAUUAGGGUAUUCUUAUGCAAUAGUUGGAAUCAAUCUUACAGAGAUGGCUUAUAGCUUACUGAAGAGUGAAGCUUUGAAGUUUCAUCUCUAUAACCUUGUUCCUGGUAUACCAACAAUGGAACACUUUCAUCAGUUUUACUGGUCUUUGAAAAACAAGAAAACAGUGGAAGAUGGGUCCCCAAGAGUAUUCCAUACUUCAGUUUUUAUAUUUGCUGAUUAUAAAAGGCAAUAUUUCACAUGUAGACACAUCUAAGAUUCAUGUAAUUUUUCUCUAGGCAUUCAUUUUCCAGCUAACUACAAAAUGUAUUUUCCCUCUUGGAUGCUGGUUAAUGAAUGCUGUUAAGGACAGACCAUUUGCAGAUUAUUUUUUUACUUUUGGAAGGAAAUUUAAUUUAGAGGAACUUUUCGCCUCCCCCUGCCUUGAAUUUCAAGGCCAAAUUUUCUUGUGGUAGGUUAGAGGUACUGAGUAACUGUUCCUAAAGCUGUCUUUACUUUCUCUGUUCCAUUCACUUUUAGUGAUAAUAUUUGAAUACUGAAGGUUUAAUUGAAUGAGUCCAUCUUCUGAAGCUAUUGUUCAGAAGCAAAGAACUCAAAUCUAGUUUUUCUUCACACAGUACUUUUCUUGAUCUUUUUAUGUCUUUAGAAUGUCAUUUGAAUGUUGGUAGCAUAUAAGAAACUACUUAGAUAAUAGGUGGCCAAAUCAUAAUUUCUUCAUCUCCAUUGUUGAAAAUAUCCAUGUCUCCUUUUCGCAGAAACUUUCCUGCCUUUUCUUACACCCUAAUUCCAGUUUUGUCUGCAUCUUAACUUUCUCUUGCAUGUGUCUGUUUCUUUCUAUACCCAUUGUAACUGUACAAUAUCAGGCCUUUGUUACUAGGUUACUAUAAUGGCCUUUAGCAGUUUUUUUGUGGUAACACUCUUCUAUUUCUUCUCCACAUUGAAAGUAUAGUUAUUUAAAAUGAAAAUCUGAUCGUUUUACUCCACUCCCAAAAAUUAUUCAAAGGAUUCCCAUUAUAAGGCCCUGCAUAAUCUGAACCUUGGUAACCUCUCCAGGCUCAUCUUUUGCCAUAUACCAGCCCCCCUCUCACCCCCACAGACUCUAUAGUGGAGGCAUCCCAGUCUUCUUUUUAGUUGCUCAAAUAUAUUAUGCUCUCUCUUGACUCUGUGCCUUUGCAAGUGACAUUCACUUGGCCUGAACACUGUUCCAGCUCCCUCUGUUCUUUCCAGGUGAUGCCUUCUCGCCUUCCAAAUCUCAGUUUAGACGUGCUCUUCUCUGGGAAGUUUAUUCAUUUACUGUGUGUUAGAUGUUGUUCUAGGCCCUGGGGAUGUAGCAGAGAAGAAGACAAAGUCACUGCAUUUGGUGAGGAGCUGUCAUCUUCAGAAUCAAAACUUCCCCCUAGUGCAGUGUCCACCUCCAGAUACUGCUUCAUUUCUCUGCUCUCUUUGUUCAUGAAACUUUUUCAAUAAUUGCUUUUUCAUUUCUUCAUCUCCAGUUUUUAUCUAAUUCCAAUUUAGUUUCUCUCUCCAUGACUCUGCUCACACUGAUUUUUCUCAGACACCAACUUUUUUUUGCCGCCUAAUACAAUCGCCAUGUUUUUUCUUCAUGUUAUUUGAUCCUUUUAGUGGCACUGGGCAUAAAUGACCACACGUUUCUUUUCGAAACAUUAUCAUGACUUUUCUGAUGCCACAUUCUCCUGGCUUUUCUUUUGCCCCACAGGAAUUCCUGUAGACAUCCACUGCCUUACUAGAUAUAGGGAGCACCUCAGGGCCCAGCCCUGUGCCCACUCCUCUCUUUAGCCCUCAUACUUUUCCUAAGUGGUACCAUCUGGUCCCUUGCUUGAAAUGCCAAAUGUGCAUUAAAUGCCAAAAUGUAUAUCUUCAGCCCAACCUCUGCUUUAAUCCCAGCAACUGUAUGUCCAGAUCCUUUUUCUCCCUUAAUGGAUAAGGAUAAAGAAUCAUAUGAGGAUGCUUAAACAAAGUAGGAGCCAAUGCAACAUGUCUUUAAAUGGAGGGAACAGAUUUCAGGUUCCUAAGGACAGCAUUGAUGAUUCUACCCAAGUGUACUGAAGAUUUCUAGCAGGCGUGAGAUGCUUUCCUUUACCAUUCCAAAGUGUUGUUGCUGGGACUUUGCUAACUUGCCUCUAAUUUUUUUUUUAAAUGAAUAUAUCCCUUGUUCAUUAGCUACCUAUUGAACAUAAAUAACAUAAAUGAGAUAUCAUGUCACACCAGUUAGAAUGGCGAUCAUUAAAAAGUCAGGAAACAACAAGUGCUGGAGAGGAUGUGGAGAAAUAGGAACACUUUUACACUGUUGAUGGGACUGUAAACUAGUUCAACCAUUGUGGAAGACAGUGUGGUGAUUCCUCAGGGAUCUAGAACUAGAAAUACCACUUGACCCAGCCAUCCCAUUACUGGGUAUAUACCCAAAGGAAUAUAAAUCAUGCUUCUAUAAAGACACAUGCACACAUAUGUUUAUUGCGGCACUACUCACAAUAGCAAAGACUUGGAACCAACCCAAAUGUCCAACAAUGAUAGACUGGAUUAAGAAAAUGUGGCACAUAUACACCAUGGAAUACUAUGCAGCCAUAAAAAAUGAUGAGUUCAUGUCCUUUGUAGGGACAUGGAUGAAGCUGGAAACCAUCAUUCUCAGCAAACUAUCGCAAGGACAGAAAACCAAACAUUGCAUGUUAUCACUCAUAGGUGGGACUUGAACAAUGAGAACACUUGGACACAGAAAGGGGAAUAUCACACACCGGGGCCUGUUGUGGGGUUGGGGGAGUGGGGAGGGUUAGCAUUAGGAGAUAUACCUAAUGUAAAUGACGAGUUAAUGGGUGCAGCACACCAACAUGGCACAUGUAUACAUAUAUAACAAACCUACACGUUGUGCACAUGUACCCUAGAACUUAAAGUAUAAUAAAAAUAUAUAUAAAUAAAUGUAAAGAGACUAAUGUAAAAAAUAAAUAAAUUUUAAGAAGAGAAUUAGCUACAAAUAAGAAAACUAAAGUUCCUUAGAACUUAAAAAAUAAAUCUUCAUAAAAUUAAAAAAAAAAAAAGAAUUUGAAAACUCCCCAAACAAUUAAGCAGUUUCCCAUAUCUCAAUAUAUACAGGAGGGUGGUAGGUUAGAAAGCAGUGCAGAAUGACCUUUGUGCAGUAUUUUUCCCCUAAAGACCAGGGAACUUGAGGAUCUGUGGGAACUGUUGCUCUCCAGCACCCUGACACCAUCUCGGCUGGCUCCUCUAUAGGAAGGACAUUAAAGUGUAAUAUCUGAGGUAGAAAAGUCAUUGUAGAACCCUUUCAGUUGCCUCCUGUCAGCUCAAUCUAUAAGAGCUGUAGAUCAUCCUGGAAACAGUGAAGCUUAUGAUUUUCAAUUAUUUUGAGACAUUAAAAUGCACAUAUGCAUAUACCUAUGUACCUUUUAAGCAGAAGUUUCCCAAAAACUUCAUUCUUAUACCCAUUACCAUUGGAAGUUUCACAUCUUAAAUAAGGUUCUGCUUUUCUUCUUAAGAGGAACCUGUUCUAACUAGAAUAAUAACUUGAAACCUUGUCUUUGAAUGUGCAUACUUUUUUGGUAGAGGAGUAGGAUAAAUUAGUUUGCACAAAUUAGUUCCAAGGUCAUAGUUUCUCUCCAGAAGGAAGAACAGUUCAGAGAUGAGUUUCCACAUUUUUUGUUUCCCUAUGAUCUGCCUUCAUCUCCCUCUUUUCCUUUGAUCGCCUUUGUUUUAAUGCGUCCUGUGUAGGAAGGGCUGGAAACGUUUGUAGUUUAGCUUUUUAGCUCCAUUGUCAUCUUGUACGUCCAAACUGUGAGCAGCUAUCCGCCAUGAUUCUGGGAAGUUACCACUAGUCCAGCAGGAGGGCUCAGGAUUUUGGGACCUCUGUCUUUUGUAUAUUCCGGUCUAGGAUGUCUCCAUUCUAGUUUUGUAGGGCCAAAAUUUUAGCUGGACUUCUGGUUUGGUGGUUCCAAAAAAAAAUAGUAACACCUCAAGUUUGUAUAAUAAAGUUAUGUCUCAAUAACAACUUUAUUGAGGUAUAAUUUAUAUAACAUAGAAUUUACCCAUCUUAAAUAUACACUUAAAUGGAUUUUAAUGAGCUAAAUUGGGUAGCCAUCAUCAUAAUCCACUUUUAGAACAUUUUCAUCACCCCAGUGAGAUACAGGUUUACAGUUAAUCCCCCUUCCUAUGAUUUUCUAAUCCUUAACCUCUGCAGUAAAUUCAUGCAGGGAAUUUCAGGUUUAGACAUUUCAUAUGGUAAUUUCUACAGAGUCUUAAGUAUUCCAAACAUCUGGACUCAAAAGGACAAAAUAUGUGCAUCAUGGAAAACAGCUCUUUUCCAUCACUUUUUGCAAAACUUUGGGAUUCUUAUGCCAAGGAUGGCCCUGCCAGUUUCCUAGAAUUUCAGUAUUUUUUCCUGUGGUUUCCUGAUGUCACAUUAAAUCACUUUAGCUAUUAUAGUCUCCGUUCUUCAAGUUAGUCUUUCUCUGACACUGAUUUAUAUUAUAGAUCAAUAGCCUCACUCUGAAGCAAGAAGUUCCUAGUGCUUUAACUUGAGCAGUUUGUUCCAGGCCCAUGUAGUCAUUUGAAUGGGCCACAUUACUGACAGUAAUGAAAAAGCAAUUUAAAGGACAUAAGAAUGGUAAAUAUCUAAAACAUAAUAACCAGAUAUACUGAAACAAAUGGUAUGGCCAUAAAAUUUGGAUAGCUAUCUGCCUUAUCAUACUAGGCAGAACAUUAAUCUCUAAAUGUAUUAAUUAGACAUCCCUAACAGUGUAUGGGGGAUAGAGAUAGCAGAUGGUAUUUCUCCAGAGGCUUCAUUUCUUGAUUUUACCCAUAUAUCAUGGUUGACAAAAAUCUGUUUUAUCAUAUAUUGAGAAUAAUCCAAAAAUCUUUCUUAAACUGGCCUUCUUAUGAAAUGAUAUUUCAGUGUGGGAAUAUGAUGAUUUUAACCAUUAAUGUUUGCUGUAUGACCAAUAUUAUUAAAAUGGGAUUUCCAUUUUACAUAGUAAGCAAUCAUGAUAGUCUAGCCACCCUUUUGUGUAAAGUCAUUGACUUUUGCAACAGAGACCACUUACAAACUGUGUGAUUUGGGGCACAUCAUUUAACUUCUCUGCACCUCUCUUUCAUCUUUGGUAGAGUGGGAAUAACAACAUAGUACUUGCAUCCUAGGGCUGCUCUGACAGUAUAUGAGCAUUUAGUGAGCACUGUAGAAAUAUUUUAAAAAAUAAUUCAAUAAAUACAUUUGAUUACAUACAAA